GGAGACACAGCUGAGGCGGCGGCGGCGGCGGCGGCGGCGGCAGCAGCGGGGCUGGGGGCGGCGAGUGGCCCGCGCGACACGCGCCGGCCUCGACCCUAUGCUUUGAUUCGCGUGGCGCAGGCGCCUACUGCCCCGCCGGCGGGGCCCGGGCUUCCUGCCGCGGGAUGUUCUCCCGAAGGAGCCACGGGGAUGUGAAGAAGUCCACCCAGAAGGUGCUGGACCCGAAGAAGGACGUGCUGACCCGCCUGAAGCACCUGCGGGCGCUGCUGGAUAAUGUGGAUGCAAAUGAUCUUAAGCAGUUUUUUGAGACCAACUAUUCUCAGAUAUAUUUCAUCUUCUAUGAAAAUUUUAUAGCACUGGAAAAUAGUUUGAAAUUAAAAGGGAAUAAUAAGUCACAAAGGGAGGAGCUGGACUCCAUCCUCUUCCUUUUUGAAAAAAUACUGCAGUUUCUACCUGAACGAAUUUUCUUUCGAUGGCAUUACCAGAGUAUAGGCUCAACUUUAAAGAAGCUUCUACACACUGGAAAUUCUAUUAAGAUAAGAUGUGAAGGAAUCAGGCUGUUUCUUCUGUGGCUUCAAGCACUUCAGACAAACUGUGCAGAAGAGCAGGUUCUGAUUUUUGCUUGCCUGGUGCCUGGUUUCCCAGCAGUCAUGUCAUCCAGGGGCCCUUGCACACUGGAGACACUCAUCAAUCCCAGCCCUAGUGUAGCUGAUGUAAAGAUAUAUCCAGAAGAAAUCACUCCACUCCUACCAGCCAUAUCAGGGGAGAAGAUUGCUGAGGACCAAACCUGCUUUUUUCUUCAAAUACUGUUGAAGUAUAUGGUUAUUCAGGCUGCGAGCUUGGAGUGGAAGAAUAAGGAGAAUCAAGAUACUGGUUUUAAAUUUCUUUUUACAUUGUUUCGAAAGUAUUAUCUUCCUCAUUUAUUUCCAUCAUUUACUAAGUUAACAAACAUCUACAAACCUGUACUUGACAUCCCCCAUUUGAGACCAAAGCCUGUGUACAUUACUACCACUCGAGACAAUGAGAACAUUUACAGUACAAAGAUUCCAUAUAUGGCAGCUCGUGUUGUUUUUAUUAAGUGGAUUGUAACCUUCUUUUUGGAAAAAAAGUAUCUAACUGCAACACAAAACACUAAAAAUGGAGUUGAUGUAUUGCCUAAAAUCAUCCAGACUGUUGGUGGUGGUGCUGUGCAGGAGAGAGCGCCUGAGCUGGAUGGUGGUGGGCCCACGGAGCAGGACAAAAGCCAUUCUAACAGCAGCACCUUGUCGGACCGAAGACUCAGCAACUCCAGCCUCUGUAGCAUUGAAGAAGAGCACCGAAUGGUGUAUGAAAUGGUACAGCGGAUUCUCUUGUCAACACGAGGUUAUGUCAACUUCGUGAAUGAAGUAUUUCACCAGGCAUUUUUGUUGCCUUCCUGUGAGAUAGCUGUAACAAGAAAAGUAGUUCAAGUGUACAGAAAGUGGAUUCUCCAGGACAAACCUGUGUUCAUGGAGGAGCCAGAUAGAAAAGAUGUUGCCCAAGAAGAUGCUGAAAAAUUAGGAUUUUCCGAGACUGAUAGCAAGGAGGCCUCAUCUGAAAGUUCUGGUCAUAAACGAUCUUCCAGUUGGGGACGCACAUACUCCUUCACAAGUGCAAUGAGCAGAGGGUGUGUGACAGAGGAGGAAAAUACAAAUGUGAAAGCCGGCGUCCAGGCUUUGUUGCAGGUAUUUUUGACGAACUCUGCAAACAUCUUUUUGUUGGAACCAUGUGCUGAAGUUCCUGUGCUCUUGAAAGAACAAGUUGAUGCUUGUAAAGCUGUUUUGAUUAUUUUUAGGCGCAUGAUAAUGGAGCUUACAAUGAAUAAAAAGACAUGGGAACAGAUGUUGCAAAUACUACUCAGGAUAACAGAAGCUGUCAUGCAGAAGCCAAAGGAUAAACAAAUAAAGGACUUGUUUGCCCAGAGCUUGGCAGGGUUACUAUUUAGGACGCUCAUGGUAGCUUGGAUCCGAGCAAACCUCUGUGUGUACAUUUCUCGAGAGCUCUGGGAUGACUUUCUUGGUGUGCUGUCCUCCCUCACGGAAUGGGAGGAACUUAUAAACGAGUGGGCCAACAUUAUGGACUCCUUGACAGCAGUGCUUGCAAGAACCGUUUAUGGAGUUGAGAUGACAAACCUACCUCUGGAUAAAUUAAGUGAACAAAAGGAAAAGAAGCAACGAGGCAAAGGCUGUGUUCUAGAUCCUCAGAAAGGAACCACCGUGGGGAGGUCCUUUUCUCUCAGCUGGCGGAGCCACCCAGAUGUGACCGAACCGAUGCGAUUUAGGAGUGCCACCACGUCUGGAGCACCGGGAGUGGAAAAGGCAAGAAAUAUUGUUCGCCAAAAAGCAACUGCUAAGCGAAGCCAGUCUAUCAGCAACUGUGUCCACCUUUCUGAGGCUUUGCCUGCCACUAAAAGCGUCCCGCUCCUCCUUCACACCGUGAGCGCUCUCUUACCUGGUCUCUCUUACUCUUCUUGCUCUCACAGGCUGUCAGAAGUGGAGGAGUGUCAACAGUCAGAAAAUGCACCUGCAGCCGGAUCUGGCCAUCUCACAGUGGGACAGCAGCAGCAGGUCCUUCGGAGCAGCAGCACCUCCGACAUCCCCGAGCCGCUGUGCUCAGAUUCUUCUCAGGGUCAAAAGGCAGAAAACACACAGAAUUCGAGUUCUUCAGAGCCUCAGCCUAUUCAAGAGAAUAAAGGACAUGUGAAGAGAGAACAUGAAGGAAUAACAAUCUUAGUUCGAAGAAGCAGCAGCCCUGCUGAAUUGGAUUUGAAAGAUGAUUUGCAGCAGACACAAGGAAAAUGUAGGGAAAGACAGAAGAGUGAAAGUACCAACAGUGACACAACUCUGGGCUGUACCAAUGAGGCAGAGCUGUCCAUGGGCCCAUGGCAGACCUGUGAGGAAGACCCAGAACUGAAUACUCCCACAGAUGUUGUGGCUGAUGCUGAUGCCCGUCAUUGGUUACAACUGAGUCCCACCGAUGCUUCAAAUUUAACAGAUAGCAGCGAGUGCCUCACAGAUGACUGUAGUAUAAUCGCCGGGGGGAGCCUCACUGGUUGGCACCCAGACUCUGCUGCUGUGUUAUGGCGAAGGGUCUUGGGGAUCCUCGGAGAUGUGAAUAACAUCCAGUCACCCAAGAUCCAUGCCAGAGUUUUCUGCUAUCUCUAUGAACUCUGGUACAAACUAGCAAAGAUACGGGAUAAUCUAGCAAUAAGCCUGGAUAACCAGUCUUCUCCAUCUCCUCCAGUUUUGAUCCCACCACUCAGAAUGUUUGCAUCAUGGCUGUUUAAGGCGGCGACACUGCCAAAUGAAUAUAAGGAAGGCAAACUACAAGCCUACAGGCUGAUCUGUGCCAUGAUGACCAGACGCCAGGACGUUCUGCCAAACUCAGAUUUCCUGGUGCAUUUUUACCUUGUGAUGCACCUGGGAUUAACCAGCGAGGAUCAGGAUAUCUUAAAUACGAUCAUAAGGCACUGUCCACCCCGCUUUUUCUCCCUGGGUUUUCCUGGCUUCUCAAUGCUGGUGGGGGACUUCAUCACGGCCGCUGCCAGGGUCCUUAGCACAGACAUUUUGACGGCGCCUCGUUCAGAGGCUGUCACUGUCCUCGGCUCUCUGGUCUGCUUUCCAAAUACCUACCAGGAGAUUCCUUUACUGCAGUCAGUGCCAGAAGUAAAUGAGGCCAUUACAGGAACUGAAGAUGUCAAGCAUUACCUCAUAAAUAUUUUACUGAAGAAUGCCACAGAAGAACCAAAUGAAUAUGCAAGAUGCAUUGCUGUUUGCUCCCUUGGGGUCUGGAUAUGUGAAGAGCUUGCACAGUGUACAAGCCACCCUCAGGUGAAAGAGGCCAUCAAUGUGAUAGGAGUAACUCUGAAGUUUCCCAACAAAAUCGUGGCCCAGGUAGCUUGCGAUGUCCUUCAGUUGCUGGUUUCCUACUGGGAGAAGCUUCAGAUGUUUGAAACCUCUCUGCCUCGGAAAAUGGCAGAAAUCCUCGUGGCCACAGUUGCUUUUCUUUUACCAAGUGCAGAGUACUCCUCAGUGGAAACAGACAAGAAGUUUAUUGUGUCCUUGCUACUCUGCCUCUUGGACUGGUGCAUGGCAUUGCCCGUGAGUGUCCUUCUCCACCCCGUGUCCACAGCAGUCCUAGAGGAGCAGCAUUCGGCCAGAGCCCCCUUGCUGGAUUAUAUCUACAGGGUUUUGCACUGCUGUGUGUGUGGCUCAAGCACGUACACCCAACAGAGUCACUACAUACUGACCCUGGCUGACUUGUCAUCCACGGAUUAUGACCCCUUCCUGCCACUGGCAAAUGUGAAGAGCUCUGAGCCAGUCCAGUAUCAUUCAUCAGCAGAAUUGGGUAACCUGCUGACUGUUGAAGAGGAGAAGAAGAGAAGAAGUUUGGAGUUGAUCCCUUUGACUGCUCGAAUGGUGAUGGCCCACCUGGUGAACCACCUGGGGCACUACCCCCUCAGUGGGGGCCCUGCCAUACUGCACAGCCUUGUCAGCGAGAACCAUGACAAUGCCCAUGUGGAAGGCUCCGAGCUGUCCUUUGAGGUGUUCAGAAGUCCAAACCUGCAGCUGUUUGUAUUUAAUGAUAGCACCCUCAUCUCCUACCUUCAGACACCCACAGAAGGACCGGUAGGGGGAUCACCAGUGGGCUCUCUCUCUGAUGUGAGAGUAAUUGUGAGGGAUAUCUCAGGGAAGUACUCUUGGGAUGGUAAGGUUUUAUAUGGACCUUUGGAAGGCUGCUUAGCACCCAAUGGAAGAAAUCCUUCAUUUCUGAUUUCGAGCUGGCAUCGUGACACAUUUGGACCUCAGAAAGACUCUUCUCAAGUUGAGGAGGGGGAUGAUGUUCUUGACAAAUUACUUGAAAACAUUGGCCAUACAAGUCCUGAAUGCCUUUUACCGUCACAGCUAAAUCUAAAUGAACCUUCCCUAACCCCAUGUGGCAUGAACUAUGACCAAGAGAAGGAAAUCAUUGAGGUCAUUUUGCGCCAAAAUGCUCAAGAGGAUGAGUAUAUCCAGAGUCAUAACUUCGAUUCUGCAAUGAAAGUCACCAGCCAAGGGCAGCCCUCCCCAGUGGAGCCCCGAGGACCCUUUUAUUUCUGCAGGUUAUUGCUUGAUGACUUGGGAAUGAAUUCUUGGGACAGAAGGAAGAAUUUUCAUCUAUUGAAGAAAAAUUCAAAAUUAUUGAGAGAGCUGAAAAAUUUGGACUCCCGCCAGUGCCGUGAGACACACAAAAUCGCAGUGUUUUACAUUGCUGAAGGUCAAGAAGACAAGUGUUCAAUCCUCUCUAAUGAAAGAGGAAGCCAAGCAUAUGAAGACUUUGUUGCUGGACUUGGAUGGGAGGUGGAUCUCUCCACCCACUGUGGGUUCAUGGGUGGCCUUCAGCGCAAUGGCAGCACCGGGCAGACGGCCCCUUACUAUGCUACCUCAACUGUGGAAGUGAUUUUCCAUGUUUCCACUCGAAUGCCGUCAGACUCAGAUGAUUCCCUCACCAAAAAGCUUCGUCACUUGGGGAAUGACGAGGUCCAUAUCGUCUGGUCUGAACACUCCAGAGACUACCGCAGGGGUAUUAUCCCAACUGCCUUUGGAGAUGUUUCAAUCAUUAUUUACCCAAUGAAGAAUCACAUGUUCUUCAUCGCGAUAACGAAGAAACCUGAGGUUCCAUUUUUUGGGCCUCUGUUUGAUGGAGCCAUAGUGAGUGGGAAGCUGCUGCCAAGCCUUGUAUGUGCCACGUGCAUCAACGCCAGCAGGGCUGUGAAGUGCCUCAUCCCACUCUACCAGAGCUUGUAUCUUUUUGCUUUAAAUGUGUAACUUACUAACCAUCCCAGAAUCAAGAUUCCUGGCAGUUUUUCAUAAGAGUGUUGGUGCAUGUUAAGAUGAAGGCAGAGCUACACUGCUCCAUUCCGAAGAAGCAUUUGGCCACUAACUGAUAAAAGAGCCAGGAUCCAUGUAUAAAUUAUUCAGAAAUUUGGUAAAUAAACAUGCAAACUUCUAGCUGGGGCUAUUGCUAUUGCAUUAUUCAGCCCAAUAAAGAGAAUUUAAUUUAAUGGAUUUUCAGCAACAUUGUUCAAUGAUCAACAAAAGGCAUACUGUCUUUUAUGAAUAACUGAUUUUCCCGGGGCAUUCUGAAGAAAGUGGGUCCUCGUUAACCCUAGAAUGGCUAGCUAAUGUAAUUGAAGCGCGACCACCUGGCAGUGAGGUUGCCCGUCAGCUGCCAAGGAAGGCCCGGGCCGGGGAGUACCAGGUGCUCUGCUCUCGCUGUCUGAUUGUUACAGUGGAAUAAACAGCGUGAUUGCACAGUAUGGCCGGGGGCGAGAAUCCAAGACUGCUGCCAACCAGAGCGCGGGCUUUCUUCCCUAGUCUUUGACAAGGGGGGCCAAAAGUGCUUCUAUUCAGAGCAGGUAAAGCUGACAAAGCUCCGAUGCUGUCUGCGCAAUUAGGAUGAAAGAAAAUAAGACUGGCCCAAGAACGAACCAGCAGUGAGCCUCAAGUACCUGUUUCUGUAUUGUACAAAGCCUAGGCCUAUUUAAUACAGGCUGGGAAGUUUAAGCAUAAAAAUUUAAAAUAAAUUCAAGAAAAAGAACUUAAAUACUCAGUGACCACUGUUUCUUAGAGCAGGUCAGCAUUAUUAUGCUUCCUGUUUUGAAGCAAAAUUCCAAGUCGUCACCAUACAAAAAACUUUAUUUUGGCCCGAAUUCCAUAGUAACCCAAAUACCCUGUUUCUUUGAUUAUACUUCAUGUAUUCUGGGCCAGGUCAUUUUGCUUUCUCUAUCUUCCUUUAUAAAGCCCUACAAGCAUCUAUAUUUAACUCACUGAAAUAGUCCUCACUCUGUGGUGUUGUUUAUUCUCAGUAAUUUUUUUUAAGUGCUGCUGCCCGUGUGGAGAUAUAAAAGAAAAUUAGCAUUAUUUGACUUGUAAAAACUUAAUUAAGAAAUAGACAUUAUGACCUAAGGGGUUUUGAAUGUGAAAUGGUUCAUUAAGUUUUUGUUAAUAGGAAAGUAAAGAGCACUUUCCCCAAACAGCAAGAACAAAAUCGCUUUCUCUUAACACAUUGAUUUAUUUCAUUUGCUAAGCACAGGAACCAUGAAAUGCUUCAUCCCAUUAGCACAUUAAAUAUGUGCAGAAGUAAAAUUACAGCUGAACAGCACCUUGUACUUUGUACUCAUGGUGUGUACAUUUCAGUAGGCUAGGAGGAAAAAACGAACUGUAGAAAGAUAAUUUUAUGGAAUUAAAUUACCUGUUUUGUAUUGCUCUGAAGCUGUGCAUGUAGCUGUGGAUUCAGAGGGACUUGAACUGUUGCCUGCGGCUUUUCACUGGAUAAUCCCAUCACCCUCCCCAGCCCACUCCCCCAGGAUCGGUAUCUAUCAUGGGAAAAUAGAAAUGAGAAAAAUGUUUCCUGUUGGGUAUUUAGUCUCUCUAGUGAUACCUAACUGUAAAAAGUGACCAGGGGCUGGGUGUGGUCGCUCACACCUAUAAUCCCAUCACUUGGGGAGGCUGAGGCCAGUGGAUCGCUUAAGCUCUGGAGUUCGAGACCAGCCUGGGCAACAUGAUGAAACCCCAUCUCUACAAGAAAUACAGAAGUUAGCUGGGCAUGGUGGUGUGCGCCUGUAGUCCCAGCUACUUGGGAGGCUGAGGUGGGAGGAUCGCUUGAGCCUAGGAGGUCACGGCUGCAGUGAGUUGAGAUCACACCACUGCACCCCAGCCUGGGUGAAAAAGUGAGACCCUGUCUCAAAAAAAAAAAAACUAAAACCAGGACUGCUUAGAAGGAUGAAUAUUAGGUCUGUGGCAUCUCUGUGUAUUAUCAGAUGGCAGUCAGGGCACUUAGUAAUAAAUUGGGAGAGUGACUUGAGCCAAGCCAGGUCACGUCUCCUAGUCUCCGUUUCCAUGCCUGGGAAAAGAGAUGGUAAAUAAAUCCUACACGAAAAGUAAUUAGUACAGGGCCUGCUAGAGACAGUGGCCUAAUGAAUGUGCUUUUCUUCCCCUUUUGCACAUUGGGCCUUUCCCAAUGAAAGGUGACCCAAAGUUUGCUCAGGAGAAACAAGAAGUCAGAAGAACAACACAAUUUUACGCCUUUUUUUCUAAAGGAUUUAUUUCUCAGCCUCCAUUUUGCAUAAAUAAGUACUCUGUAAGGAUGAAGUAAAUAUAUAUGAAUUUAGUUGUUUGGGGGGAAAUACAUAUAUAUAAAUAAUUAGUCCGUCUUUUAGUCUGAUAGCUUGAAACUCCAUUUUGUUUUCAGUCAAAUGUGAGAGUCUUCCUGGCAACCCCAGCUUGACCCUGUCUUUGGAUCUGGAGCUAGAAACCCAGAUUGGACAGUUGGCGUGCGUGCAGUCCCGAGCGCACUGCCUGGCAGCCCCGGGCCCAUGCUGCCUGUGGUCCCUGGUGGCUGAGUCACCCUGAUCACUGCCUCUGAGGGCUGUACCGUGAACAUACCCUGGAACUUAGCAGGGACACUAAAAGGGAUAAAGGGAGUCAGUCCCAAAGGCAAUCUCUCAACCUUCUUUGUGCCAUGGAUGUCUUGCACUUCUCAGAAUGUUUGUAAAUGCAGAACAUAAAGCAUAUAGGAUUCCAGAGUACAUCAGUUAUAGUGAAAUGCUUUCUAAAGCAAAUGCAUAUAUAGUAAUAUAGGAAUGCCUUUAUUCAUGCAUUAAAUACCAAGCUCUAGUAGUAGGUCCAAUAAUCAUUAUAAUUUUGAAGCAGUAAUGAGCAGAAUCAAUAUUUUGAGACACUGGUAACAAUAUAAUGCGUCAUGAAAAUAUCUGAUUUCUACUGGUGACACAGUCACAGGUAGUAUCACUGUGGUAUGUUCCUAUUUAUAACGGAAAGAAAUGUUUCAUUUCAGCUAGAGGAUAGGAUAGUGAGAAUGAAGAUGUGCUUUUUUACCAUCCAAGUUCAGGGACCCCUGGAAUUUUGAUCAUCACCCAGAAGAUCCCCAUGGGGUCCAUUGACCCAUAUUAAGAACCACUCUUUGCGGGAUUCAUAAGAACCACGGAGUCAGGAUCCACUGGAACCACUGCAGUGUUGUUCCUUCAGCCAGCUAGCCUGCGAGAGUGGUUUCUGAGACUCUGUAGGUAUGGGGCCUGUUCUCUGGGUGCUAGAUAUACCACAGUUCCUGCCCGCAUGGAACUUCCAUUCCAGUGGAAGAGGCUGACAGCAAGCAAGCUAGAUCAUGAAAAUCCAGGGAAGUUAGAGCAUGGUGAGUACUGAGGAGAAAAAUGAAGCCAAGAAAAGGAGAAUGAAGGGUCUGGAUCACAGUGCCUCCUGAGAAAAGCUGGCAUUUGAGCAAAGACCUGAAGGAGGUGAGGGAGGCAGCCAGACAGGGGUCUUGGAAGAGCAUCCCAGGCAGAGGGCACAGCACACACACAUCGUGUGUGUGAAGUGUGGGAAGGGCUCCACACCACAGAGGUGACAGCAGGGGCAGGCACCCAGUGGGGCAGGGCCUUGCCAGCCACAGUAAGGACUUCCGCUUUUCCUGUGAGGUGGGAGCCAUCUGAAGGCUGAACGGAGGACGGCACCAUCCCUGAAAGCCUCCUGCUGCUGGGUACAGAGGCCAGAAGAGGUAGGAGGCCACAGCCAUAAUCCAGGAACGAAAUGACAAUGGCGUGGCCUGGAUGGUGGCGUGUGGUGGUGACAAGUGGUCAGGUUCUGGAUUGAUGGGGAUUUGUGGCCAGAUGAGACGUGGCAUGUCAGAGGGUGCAGAGUCAUGUGUGCCUCAGUGACCAGGCGGUCUUCAGGACGUUCAGAGUGGUUUGUGGUUGCCAGUCUCCUUAAUUUCCCCAUUUACAGGAGGUGAACUUCUGUUUGAAUUAAUAAUGCCAACAUUUAUUGAGCUAACAUUUAUGAAAUUAUACAUAUUAUGUAUUCCCAUGUGAACAGAUGGUUUGUGUUCAGAUGCCAUUGUGCAGAGGAGGCCACAGGACCCAGGGAGGAUGGGGACCUUGCCAAGGUCCCACCGGCAGCAUUCAGAGCUCGGAGCCUCCCGUCAGUUAGUUAGCCCCGGAGCUUGGUCUCCCCGGUGCGGCUGCCAUGAUGGCCAAUGCACAGGCUCGGAUGAGGUGGCGCCCUGGCCGCCCGCCCGUGGCAGGGAUUAGAUCAGGCAUGGCACAUGAGUGUGUCUGGCAGGACGUAGUGGGCAGUCAAAAUGGCAGUUUCCUGCCUCCCUCCCUUCCAGGAGCCUGGGGCUUGACGCAUUGCCUCUCCCAGAACGCUACUCACCCGACUAGGCCAGGGUUUUAUUCUUUUUUCUAUUUAGAUUACUCUUCGGCCUCCAACCUUAUGGCAGCAGAGACGACAGUGUCAACACAUUGAAGCCUUCGUGAGCCAUCCAGUGUUUGUCUCCCCAGGGGAAGUGAGAUGGCUUCCCUGGGCUGGUGUUCUAUGCCUUUGUGUCCUGGCCAGGGCCCAGGACCGGCUGAUGGCAGGGACACUUUGCCGUCUUACUCAUGUAUUGCCGUGACGCUUAAAUACACUUUAUCAACCACUACCAGUUUUUUCUUCAUAUUAGGGAUGGCAUUGGAAGAAGGAAUAGAUAAGUAACGUGUUUGAGCAAAGAAAGAUCUACCCUAUUAAAUUGUUUUAUCUGGUAGGGAUGGUAUUUAAAUAGACUGAAAUCUUUUUAGAAAACUCAUGCAAAGCACAUGUGUAGAGAACUUGAUCUGAUUUACUUGGAACAUGGAAGUACUAAGGAUUUCAGUAGCUCUGGUUUCUUCGUGGGGUUUUAUUUGAAGGGUCCUGGAAGCACUGUAUGCUGGAGGCUGCUGUAUUUCCUGAGGAGCAAAGUGGCCUGAGAGAGAGGGAGCAAUGUCCACAGGCAGGUCUGUGAUUUAGGCAGACAGACGGGGAAAUGUCUGGGGCCCAGCGGGCUUUUCCAAGUAAUCUGUUACUGUCUGGUAUUAGGGUUAGACCAUAUGAAAUGCUGCUUUUGCAGGUUAAAAAUCAGCAAUUUUGUAUGAUUCAACUUGAUACAUAACUCACCCCAUUUCAAGACUUGAGCAGCUACAGUAUUUAUGGGAUUGUUCAUUUAAACAGAACUUAGAACAAUAAAUUUCUAAGAAUUUUUACUAAUCCUGCUCACAGACUAAUCUUGAUUCUUGUCCAUGUGAGCUCAAUCCAGAGCAGUCCCUGAAAGGCCAUAGAUCUAGUGCAGUUCCUGCCUGUGGCAGUGUCCACAGACACAUCCCAGUGUCGGGGUCCCUCGUUCCCUUCGUGAAGAGAACAGAGCCACCUCUUUUCACCACACUGGGACUCCGGGGCAGCAUCAGCCUGCCUCCUUCUUUGCUAAAAAUCACACUGUGCCACAUCUUUAUCCUGCCCCCAAGUGGAGAGACGCACAUGCUCCUCCCACUUUGCUAUGGCACAGCAUUGUCAGCUCUGCAGCAGCCAACAUUCUAGUAAGGGUGUGACCCCUGUUCCCUACUCUUCUCCUUCAGAUAUAAUAUGAUUCCGUACACUUUAUUCAAGAGUUCAUUCUUUACUGUCCUUCCUUUUUUGCUCUGUAUUAGCUGCAUUUAUGUAAAUUUUUCUCCCCCAAAUGACAGUGCCCUUAACUGUAGAUGCUGUUAUGCAUCCUUUUCCUCAGCUGCUCCCAGCAUCUAGCAGAGUACGCGCUGUCUGCCCAGGGUGGUGAACACCCUCCAUCUCUGAAGUGUUGCUUCUGCCUCUGCGUCAUGGACUUUAGUUCCAUAUUGUUGCAGCAUUCGCCUGUCCCUCCCAUGCCUCCCAUGACCAUUUUCUUCAUCCAGGGCUGAGUUUAGAGCCAGGGGAUCUGGCAUCAACACCCAGGUGGCUGUGCAGGGCCUCCUUGAGGAAAAGGGUCUGCAGUAUCCACCACUUUUAGAUACCUUGCACCUCAAGCAUUGGCAAACAUGGCAUUCAAGAAUCGUAGGUGAAGAACAGAGUCCACAUUGGAGCCAUCUCUCUGUGAUGUCCCGUCAGCUUCUGGGCAUGGGGUAGGACACAGGAGAAUAACUUGUAGAUUUGUUUUUCAUAAGUUCACUUUGAAUGCCUUUCUCUAAAAGAAAACUUUUUUGAGACAUGGUCUCACUGUGUUGCCCACGCUAGAGUGCAGUGGUGCAAUCACAGUUCACUGCAGCCUUGACCUCCCAGGCUCAAGCGAUCCUCCAGCCUCAUCCUCCCAAGUAACCAAGACUACAGACAUGCACCAUCACACCCAUCUAGUUUUUAAUGUGUUAGUAGAGACGGGGUCUCAUCACGUUGUCCAGACUGGCCUCAAACUCCUGGGUUCAAAAUAUACUCCUGCAUCAGCUUCCUAAAGUGCUGGGAUUACAUGCAUGAGCCACUGCUCCCAGCCUCUAAGAGGAAUUUUAAUAUAGUCCUCUACCCAAACAGAUGAAAGGCAAUGGCAGACUGCUUUAAAACAAACACAUCCCAUGCAGAACGUGGUCAUCUCCUCCUGGUCUUCACUUCUGAGCAUUUGGCCAUGCUGGUGGCCUCCGUCUGUUUUUAGUGUUAGGAUAUCAGAGGCUCACCUGCAUCCAUUUCUGGUUGUGGCUGAAACAGUCCCCUGCACAGCUCACAGGGGACUGAGAGUGUUUCUGCUUGCUUUUAAGGUGCUUUUUACAACCUUUUCCAUCUCAUCAGGCUUUGAACUUAUUAAUUUUAAAAUCCAAGGCCUCGUUGCUGACUGUGGAUUUUAGCUCUGCACUUUUCCCGGGACCCCCACAGAGGAACUACUGGCAUUUCCCAUGAGUUCCCAUGAGAGGCCAGUGUGUGUGGCUAUGAGCAACUUUUGUUUGGGAGAGACUAACCAUGUGUAUUAAAAUUUGUUUUAUUUUUGUCUUCAUUUUGCUUUUAUACACUUUAUUCCUCACUGCUGGACCUUGCUAAAUUACUAGAGCUUUGAUUUUUCAGGGGCUUUUUCAGGCCCCCAGAUGAACAAGUCAUGGACUUCCCAGUACAUCACCACCCCUUCUCCCUCUUCCUCCCUACUACAGAGAGCUUACAACUGCAUGCCAUGUCUGAGUACAAAGAACAUGGCCAAAACCUUCAUCUACAUGGCUGUUAAGUAUACUUUACUAUAUAAAAUACAUAUCAUGCAGUAUUUUGUUAUUUGAUCUACUUUCUGUUCUGAUAAAUUUCGGAAUUUCACUGAUGUAUACUGGAUUUUGAAGUAUUUUAGCACUUGUCUGUUGUGUGGUGAAGCAGAGAUGCUAAUCCUGGUCCUUCGUGAGCAUCGUCUUCAUCUCACAAAAACAUCCAGACUAUCUCAUUUAUCAGCUGACCUUGUCUCUGUGGUCCUUUGGUCAAAGGUCUUUGUGGUCCUUUUUAAGUAAGGGCUUAUUUUAAAUGAGCUGAGUAGGUUUGUUUGGGGAGUACUUAUACUUGUUGGACCUCAUCUGAGAAACAUUUCAGCCUCAUGAGAUAAGUCAAACUGUUGGUGCAGCUUGCACAGAAAAGUACUGCGUUUUUAGGUUGCAUUUGUAUUGAUACCUUACAUCAAAGAGCUUAUUCCUGUUUUCUCACAGGCUAGCAGCCUCUGGAGAUAUCCUGUGCCUGGCUGCAGCUUCUCCAAAUCCCCUCAGCCCCUUGCAGGGUUUGAGUGCUCCUCCUAGUUUCUUUCUCUCACCUCUUUUAAGAUAUUGUAUGAGAAGCCCCUCCCUGCCCAACCACCUUUUUGGGCUCUGGUUAAAUUACUAGGUGGAACCAUAUGAAAUUGCUAAUAUUGGUUUGCCUAUCACCUAAUCUUGAACUCGGAGCCUUAAUUUCUUCAGCUAUAAAGUGAGAGUAACAAUACUUUCUUCAUAGGAUUUUGUGAGAAUUAUUCAAGAUAAUUUGGGCACACAAUUGACUGGCACAUAGUAGGACUGAUAAUUAUGUCUGAAUGGAGAGACAAAUGGAUAGAAGUGUUACUAGAUGUUUGUUGGCAUCACAUGAAAUGACCCAAUGGCUUGCCACUAAAUUUGCAUAGUCAUUCUUAAAAUGCAGGCUCUUUAGAAUGGGGAGAAUUCACUUAGGAGAUUCUUGGUGCUCACGAGUGAGCCAGAUGUGCACCUCCAGACAGCUGGAGCGGAGGCUCUGCCCAUGCACCAAGUGCUGCUGGGCAGUCAGAUCAACCAGUCACUUUCACAUGGACAGCUUGAGGGUGGACAAUUGCAGAGUUGGAGUAUUUAAUGAUAAUGAUGAUUCUCCCUGGUAAAAAGAGGAAGCGGGCUAGUUUUAAAAAAUAUUCAGAAAUGAGGCUAUUUGGAGAGAUUAGAAUUCAUUUUUUUUUUCAAAAUCAUUCUAAAUAAAUAAAUAGUUUUUUGUUUUCCCAUGUAUGUAUAGCAUGGUGGAAUGUAUUUUCCAGUGUUUCCGAAUAUUGAAAUAGUCUGCUAUUUAGUCUCUCUCAAAGAAUCAUUAACUUUACAUCAAGAUGUUCUAAGGAAAUGCUGUGGCUCUUGUUUUUAAUUUUCUUCCACUCAGGGGGAUUAGGUGGCAUUACCAAGUGAUUUAAAAAUCCAGGUAGGUGCCUUUAAUUUGUGCUGAAAAAAUCCAAAAGCUCAUUAAGUGACUUGCUGAAAUGAAUAUAUACGGCGCUCACCUUUGAAAAGGUUAGCACCGUCACGAGCUCAGGGAGCCACUGCUUGGUCACUCUCCACCCUGCCCUUAGUUGUUUAACCCAUGGUAAUCACCUGGUUUGUGACACAAGGCAGCUCCUUAUAACCAGCAAAGGAGAGCCCUGGCAGCCCUCCACUACAGGCACAAUGAGACAGUCACAGUCUUGGAUCCGUCUCUGUAGAAAAUGUACCUACGUGUUUUAUUCCAUAGUGGUCGGGUCAUCAAGGGAAAAUAAACAUAGCUUCCUCUCAUGAAUUCUGACAGUGAAGACGAUCACCAGCCUUGGAACAACGGUGGUUCCUAUUUCACAGUCCUUACUGUUUCUCGCACCAACUGCUUCUUUAAAAAAUUACAUGACUUUAAUGACCAAAAUAUAAUUUAUUAUUAGUUACAAGUUAACUGAUGUAUAACCCAUUUAUCUCUCCCAUUAAGUCUGUGCAAGUAAUAUUAGUGGAUGUUUCUCAUUGAAGAUAGCCCCUACUUCAACUUUGCAUAGAGGAAAAACCCGGGACACAGGCCUCUUGUAGACAUUAUGGCUGCAUAGAGAGGUGCACACAUGCUAUAGAAGUGACAUUUGGAACCAUCAGAUAAUAAUUGCAUAUAUUUAUGGGGUACAGUGUGAUGUUGUGAUACAUGUAUACAUUGCAGGUUGAUUAGAUCAGGCUAAUCAACUAUUACUUCACAUACUUACAUUUAUUUGUGGUGAGAACACUUAAAAUCUGCUCCCUUUGCAAUUUUGAAAUCUAUAAUACAUUAUUACCUACAGUCACCAUGCUUAAUUUUUUUGCAUAUGGCCAUCCUCCCAUCUCAAGGAUAAUUUUAGAGUAAUUUAUUGCCAGUUUGCAAAUUGUGUCAUACAUUUUAAAAUUAUAUAAAGCCUGGUGCAUGUUUAAGUUUUGGUUUUCUCUUGCAUCAUCCAUUAAACCUGUCUGGUCUUUGAAAUGUCCUCUACCUGCCUGGGAUCCUCUCCCUCUGCCCAGAGCCACUUUCCAAGGCUGUGUCCAGGGCUUUCUGUACAGAUCUCUGUGCUGUGGCACCCUUCCUUCUCCCCCCUCCAGCCUCAUACCUGGCUGCCAGACUCACCACCAUGCAUUGUCAGCCUGCUGUCUACCCUCAGGAGCCUCCUCGCUUCCCUAACAGCAGUGUCAGUCUAGACUCCGGCCUCUCUCCAGUCCUACUUCUUAAGGAGCCCUGUGUUCCCCAGUUCUCUGGGCAUGGCUUCUUGGGAAAUGCCCCAUGAUGUUUUCCUCCUGCCUCCCCCAUCACUCCUGUUCUGGCCUGUGUAGAUUCCACUCAGUCUCAGAGCUACGCUUCAGGGGGACUCGCUCCACAAAGCCCCCAACCACACCAAAAGGGUAUAGCCAUUUCCUUCUCAUGAUGCCUUGCACAUUUGUUCACACCACCAAGAAGCCCUGGGAAGAGUGUCCCAAAGUCAUUCCUGUCAUAUCAGUAGUAUGCUGGGAGACGAUAGGGACCAUGAGUUAACGUCUUUAUGUCCUCCAUGAACUCACAAAAUAAUUACUUCUGAUUGAAAAUAUAUAGAGGCAUUUAAAAAGUUCUCUCGCUCAUGUACUGUCCUUAACCUUUGGGGUCUACGUAGAGUAUAUACUGAGACCAGGUGAUCCCAGUGAUGUACAUACGUGAUGUUUCAUGAAAACAGUGAGAUCUUGUGUCUGCUAUCAACAUACAGACACAGGGAACUCCGAAAGGUAAAGGCAGUAGAGAAAUACAAAGGAAAUUUCUCAAGUGACAUUUUUAAUAUUCACUGGAGAUGAGUGAAAACAGUUGAAACAUCAGUCUACAAAGUAAAUCACCAGUAUACUUGAUCAGGAUCAGAACCUGCUAUAGGUAGAGGCAAGUUUCCAUCAUGUACAAUGACUACUCUCCUUAUCACUGGUCCCUGUGUUUCUGUUUUUAAUUGAGAAAAACACUUCUCAUGAAAUAUUCCCCCACCUGUUGGAGGAAGCAUUCAGGCCAUGGGACAAGGAGGUGAUGUGGCCCUUUCCCAUAAAGGGAAAGAUCUUGCUGCCCUAGGCCUCCACAGGGCCCACAACUUUGAGCCAGAUGCCUGGCCACGGUAGUCAGUGAUUGAGUGGCACUGAGAUCCAGGCCUGCCCUUGUGUCCCUACUCUGGAAUGCCAGGGCUCUACUCCACGUUGCUGUUUUGCCAGCUGCUCCCUGUUAGGUUCCACUGACCGGGUGCCACUAGGUCCAGCAGCUGCUGCUGUGAUCUUGAACAGGCACACCUGUGGCAUCAUUCCCCUCACUGCAGCAUGGUCCUGCAGAUCAGCCCUGAACCCCUCUUUCACAGAUGAGGGGAUGCAGGUUCUGCAGGGCAAACUAGUUGCCUGAGGUCACAGGGCCAGGACUCAGAGGAGUCUGCAUCUGAACUCAGGGCUUUGACUUCAACCCUGCUAUCUGUGAUGACACAUGAAAUAUCAGGCCUGAAUUUCUACCUUCUUUUUUGUUCAGAGUCAUUGCACAGGUGCUUCUACCCUCUUCAGGGUUUUUGAAUGACACCAAGUGGCACAUAAUUAAAAAUAAGGAUUUAUCAGAAAUGGUUCACCCCCUUGGAAGAUAGCAAUGAAAGAAUGACAGUUCAUUCCUGUUCCUCUCAGUGUUUUGAUUAUGGUGCAAAAGGCCUUUACCGUGAGACGCUCUGCUCUCCAGUGUUGAAGCAUGUCACGACUUCAGAAGCCACAUCUGGCACCAAAUUCAUUCUCUCUUUGAAAAUGUCCAUUCAAAAUAAUUAAGAAAACUUUAGAAUUUUGUACUGAUUGUCUUCAAAAUAUCACUGGAAAUAAUUGCAGAAAGAUAAUUUUUUGUGUAAAUGAGGUCAUGUAAAUUUUUCAAAUCUUGCUGCAUGAAGGAAAGAAUCAAAUUAAUGUAGUUUAUUCCUCUAAAUUGUAGCUUCUUAUGACAAUUGUACAGAUAAUGAUUUAGCUAGAAAGUCACCAUUUAUUCCAGAUUAGCUAUAAAAAUGGCCAGUUUUGUGCUACUCUUGGUUCUGGGGGGAGAAAGAAGAAUCUAAUUUAUCUAUCCUUAUUCUUCCUGUUAGCACCAAACAACAAUGUUUGUGGAUUAAUUUAGCACUGAACAUUGCAAGCAUCUUAAAUAAGUUUGAAAGAUUAAACUGAGACAGCAUAAGGGAGUAGGAAGAGGCCAGCAUGUGUAACAGAUCGCCCUGGGUUUGAGUUUCAGCCCUGCUCAUUGCUAGCUGGGUGGUCUCAGAGCAUCACUUUUGUUGCCUGUCUCUGCUUUAUCAUAUGUGGUUUGAGUUUUGCAGGAGGACCCAAUGGGCUCUUGGCUACAAAGAGCUUCAUGAGUGGCAGCCAACUGCACCAACAUUGGGUAGCUUGUUUUUAUUUCAUAGAGAUUGUCUCUUUUAUUCUAAGUGAGAUGUUGCCCCAACAGAACUCAGGCUAAUUAUAGUGUAAUCUCACUAUGAUGGGUUUUAGAAUCCUCCAAUAUACUAUAAUACUCAGUACAACAUUUGAAUAUUAUAGGAUCAAAGAUUUAGAGGAGGGCUGAGAUGCAAGGAAGUACUUUCCUUACAUCUGAGGAGAGAAUAAUGGAUAUGUAGGAGGCACUUAGUAAAUAUCAGAUGGAAGGGUUGGUGAGUAGAUGGGUGAAUGGGUGGGUGGGUGGGUGGAUGGAUGGAUGGAUGGAUGGGUGGGUGGGUGAAUAGAUGGGUGGCAGGCACAAUAAUGGGAAGAAAUGAGGGAUUGAGAGAAGAUGAACCUGGGCUCUCUGAUGUGGAUGGGCCACCACAUUUGGGAUCAUGUCCAGCCUCCUGGCCUUGAGACCAGUGAUACAAUUCUGCCUCACAUAUGAAUUGUGAGGAUCAUCUCCAUGGCUCUUCAAAUAAAAUACAAAAUGGCUCCAAAGGACAUUUUCCUCAUCUGGGUCAUGUCUCAUGCCAUUAAUAUAAAACUGCUGAUUUAAUGGAGCUGCUUUUGAUCUAUCAAGAAAAGACGUACCGAAUUCAAUUUGGCUAUUUUUUUUUCUAAGAGUAAGUGUCUUAAUUUGCAAGAGAAUGAUUUGAUUAUAAUUUUAAGUAAUACUGCAGUUAUAUUUUUAGUCACGAAGAUGAUAUCAAGUGACUCUAUGAGGCUUAAAUGUGGAAAGUCCCAGAGAAUUGUGUGGGUUGGGAAUUUUAUCUUUAACAGCACUGGGGGCUGUUUCUGUUAUUUGUAUAUUUUAUGAGUUUAGGCAGAAUAGAUGGGAUCUGUUACAAGGAAUUUUGCAUAUAAAAUAUAAAAGCAGACAGUUUUCAUUGAAGAGUAAAGUAGAAUUAUCCCAGAAUAUAAAGACAUAAAAAGUUAAGAUAAACACCCAUCAUUUUUUUCUGAAAUUUUAUUUUUAAAGCAUGUGUUAUUAUGAGAGAAUUUCUAAUUCUGAUCUCUCUUCUGACUGCAGCAGACUUUUUAACCUGAAUUCCUUCUGCCUUACUCUUAAAAGUUGAAAAGAUUUAGGUACUCAGAGGUACCUGCUGAAAUGGAGUAGAAAUGUUGAAUCUGUUGUUCAAAUGUCAGAUUCAGGAAGGACCAAGUAUCUGCUCUGCACUUGAUGAUAUAUGUUGUCCAGCUACAAAAGAAAACACCCCUUACAAAAAAAAAAAAUCUUUUUUCCCUUGCACAAUCCAUCCUGGGCCAGAUAUAGUCAUAGCUCAAUAGAAAAUUGCUUUCCUGUUACUGGCAACCUGUGCGGUCACUGGUAUGACAGUGCCUCACGUCAAAUUGCAAGCCGAGGGGCCACUGCAGCAGGUGCAUGGUAACGGUGCCCAGGAGCACUGGAGGACAUGAAGGACACACAAGGCACCCAGUGCUGUACACCACCACUUGAAACGGGGCACCAGGACCAGGGGCAGGAAGACAGCAGCCCCUGGGCUAGCCGGUCGGAGGGAGUUCUAAUGAAGGGAUGAGUGACAGGGGAAGAGACAUCUGCAUGAAUAAGUGCAGGACGCAGGGCUGAUGUGCUGUGCUGCAGACGCUCCCACCCCGCAAGCAGAAUGGCACACAGAUGGGAUUUAGUGAAACUGUCACUCCCGCCUCUGCUCUAACCCACAGGGAUUUCUCUCACUGGCUUGUAAGAGCCAAAAAUACUUGAAAUGCAAGUAUUGAAGUUUAAUUUGCAGGAGAAAACACAGUAAGUUUUCUUUCACCUGAAGUUGUUGGAUAAUAGAGUCCCAACUGGAGAGAGUGGAAGAAGGGCUACAAUUUACUCCUUCAGCUUUCUAUGAAAACAGCAGUGAGUAGAUGGAACUGGGUCUUCUGCUAGUUUUGGCCUCACUAGUCUUUUCUCUUGUUGGGAGAAUUCUGAUCAUAAGAGGCAGGGCCGUGACUGAGAGCCAGGCUCUCAAGUCAGGCUGCUGGUAGCAUCUGAGAGAGGUGGAACAGAACACUUUUCCUCACUGCUCUUCAAUUUCCUCCUCUACAAAAAAAUUAGGAUAGUACAAACCACAGAAGGAAGUUGUGAGGAUUAAAUGAGAUAGAGCCUAUAAAACUUCAACCCAUUAAAAGCACUUGAUCAUUUUCAUUGGCAUCUUUAUUUAAAUGUAAUCUUUGGUUGAUGCAGCAUCAGCAGAGGUGCCUGGCCGGGGGCUCACUUAUGCUCAGGAUGUAGUCUGAUUCACCUGCUGCAGACGCCACACCUGAAGGGCUGUCAGAACAGGGACUUUUUCCUUUGAGGUGCAUUCGUAAAAGGGCAUCCCGUAUGCUGUGUGUUGCUGAUGAUCUCUGAGAUUAUGUCAGUGACGAUGCCUGAACUUCACACUUGAGCCCUGUUGCUUCUUAAGCCUUCCUCUAAGAUCAUUACAGUGUUUCCCUUCCUCACCCCUAAGCAGAAGCAUCACAGGGCUGUAUGACCACCUUGUGGGGUUCUCAGCCCAGUGCCCUUCAGCCAGAGACUCGUUAGCAAACAGGUGGCUUCACUACCCCACUCAAACACGUAGACCUUCAUCAAGACUCAUUAUUUUCAACAGAGCUAUAUGUGUAUAUUUUUUUCUUUACACAGCCUAGAACCAGAUUAGCAGAAGGUGUAGAACAGUACAAUUGAGCCUGUUAUGAAACCAGAGUAAGUCAUUCCAGCAGCCCCUGGGAAUUUUCAUGACCAAUCUUGACAGCAAACAUAAAAAUUUCAAACCACACUAUGUAAGUCACUUAUAUAUACUUCCUGAUCAUCUUUAUUUUUUUUAACCUAACAGUGAACCAAAUGUUAGAACAGAUGUAAAAGGAGUAAAAGAGUUGCUUUUGCCCUGUGGCUGCUCAAAACUACUUUCCAUAACAUUAAUGAGACCCAUAUUCUCCACGCUCAUCUGGUCAUUCUGGUUUGCACAGGACCAGUGUCUGUUGAGGGGCCCAGCCAUGCCUACAGAUGGAGCAGCUCUUCAGAGUGCUGCAGAUAAAGACAUGCUCCAGGGCCGUUUGUUGUGAUGGCUCAACCCUUGUGUCCACUUAGUGUAGCUUCUUCCUAAGUGAGCCAGUUGCAUCACAUGCUGUUAUUAAUAGCCAGAAAUCAGUUGCUUUUAAUAUUAACUGGCCAACAUACUUUUGCUACUUCUGAUCAUGAGGGAGCUUUGUGUUAUUAGAAUUCCCCCAAAUUUCCAGUGAGGUUUCAAUAAUUGUGGCAUUAUUUUUUUUGCUCUGAUAGGUCUGUGGGGUGUAUUGAGUUUCAAGUGUGGGUCAGCAGUAAUAUUUAUCACUCAGGUGUGCUUUGCAACCCAGCGUACCACUCAAGCAGUCUGAAUCGGCCAGGAAGGCCGCUUGGCAACCUUCACAUCAGCUUCUUUCCUCAUUUUGUAAGUCACUUUCAUUUGGUAAACCCCUAACUUUUCUUGGAGUUUCUUCUUGACAUCUGAUAACUUGGUAUCAGAUGAAUAUCUUCCUGGAAAACUGAGAUGCCUUUAAGCUAUUAAAAUUAUUUCAUAGAAGCAUAGAAAUACUAUUUUCUGCUUCCAGAGGUAGUGAUAUUUAUUAUUUUAAAACGCACAGAAGAAAAAACAAAUAAAGCUAAACUUUUGUAAAUACCAUGAAAAGGAAUUAUUUCCCCAAAAUUGCUUUCAGAAAUGAAAAACGAAGAAAAUCUGUACACAACUUGGUGCAAAUACUUUGGACCACAAAAUUCAGUUGUGUCGUGCCUGAGCCUAGUCUGAUUUCACGUGGGCCUAAGAGAUUGUUUAUAGGUAACAAUUAAGAAUGUCUCAAAGGAAUGGAUAACCAGAGUAUCUGCUAUAGAUGUUUUCUUAUACUUGUCAGUUUCAUUUACUUGUUAUCUAUCGUAUAUCAUAUAUCAUGAUCCUAUUUAAUUUCUAGAAUCAACCUAGAUAUGAACUAUUCUGUAGGCCAAAUGAAAGUCGCUUUUGCCUUCAAAAUAGAAUGGUCGAAGAGUAAACAUUGGAUAAUUCAAUUCAAAUUAUGUUGCACUAAAUAGUACCUGUAACGUAUUUUAUUUAAUAAUAUUUUUUUCUCUUAGAGUCAGUGAUGAUAGAAACAGAGUUUACAAUUCAUGUGUGUUGCUCUUUAAUUGUCUACUCUUUUUAUACUUUGCCACAAACAGGAUUUAAGACAUUUAGAGGCAGUUCUGCAUUUCUUCUUUUUUUUUUUUAAUUAUACUUUAAGUUUUAGGGUACAUGUGCACAACGUGCAGAUUAGUUACAUAUGUAUAUAUGUGCCAUGUUGGUGUGCUGCACCCAUUAACUCAUCAUUUAACAUUAGGUCAGUUCUGCAUUUCUAAUUAUUUUCCGUUUUGUUGUCACUUCAUGGAUAUUAAAUGCCCCAAAAAUGUCAGCAGUGGUCCUUUCUAUAUUAAGGUUGGGAGUACAUUUUUUAGCUUCUAACAUAUGAUGUCUUUAGGACGAGUGAAAAUCUGUGAAAGAGAAACACGGUUCAAGUGACAUUGACUCCCUUCCUCCCAGAAAUCAAGUUAUUGGCGUCAGCAUGGCAGAACUCAGGGCUUCUAUUGUUCAUAUUGAUUCGUCACUUUUUCUGUCGUUUUCAUCAUUGAAGUAGCCUGUUGAAUCUUUUCUCACUCAAUUUGACAGCACUUUCUCUAGACUUGAAAUAGGCUGAAUGACGAAUUUUCUUGUCACUUACAUUUUUACUGAUGUGAGACUUUGAGCGACGGUGUCACGGGGCAUUUUCUCACUUGGUGAUUUGCAGAAGGUGAGGUGCACUGGGAGAAUUGGAGAAGAUGGAAAUGGAAAAUGCUAUAAUUAAGGAUGUGCUCCUUCACAAAUCAAUCCCCUGGGAAGAACUGAUUUGAACAUUUCUAAUAACAGCAUAGUCCAAAUCCGUUGCAUGUGUGGAGCGCCUCGGAUUCUAGGAGGGAGACCUUCAGCUCCCUAUGCCGGAAGGACAUAGGAAUAUGAGAACAGACCAUCUCCAAAAGUCUGUAAUUUAAUAGCCUGAAGAAAAUCUUUUUCUCAUUUCCAUUUGCUCUUAUCAUUUCCUCAGAAUUAUUCUUAAACUUGGUUAUAUGGUAUUUUCUUCUUUUUGAGCAGUAGUGGACUGUUUCUCUCCAGGAGUGUAUCAUUAGGGUUUGAAACUUAAUCUAAUAUCUUAUACCUCCAUGUGUUUAAUUUCCUUUUCCAAAACAUCCAUUUUAUUUGGUUACAUUGUUGAGUAAAGUCAUCCUCUUUACCUGUUACCAGGCUGUGACAUUUACUUUCAAUGAUUCAUUUAUUUGUGGCCUUAAACAGUCCUAGAAUUUAAAUUUACAUUAUAUUGAAA